GGAUCACGCAGGCGCGGCUUUCAGGCCAACAUGGCCGUGCUGCUGCUGCUGCUCCGUGCCCUCCGCCGGGGUCCAGGCCCGGGUCCUCGGCCGCUGUGGGGCCCAGGCCCGGCCUGGAGUCCAGGGUUCCCCGCCAGGCCCGGGAGGGGGCGGCCGUACAUGGCCAGCAGGCCUCCGGGGGACCUCGCCGAGGCUGGAGGCCGAGCUCUGCAGAGCUUACAAUUGAGACUGCUAACCCCUACCUUUGAAGGGAUCAACGGAUUGUUGUUGAAACAACAUUUAGUUCAGAAUCCAGUCAGACUCUGGCAACUUUUAGGUGGUACUUUCUAUUUUAACACCUCAAGGUUGAAGCAGAAGAAUAAGGAGAAGGAUAAGUCGAAGGGGAAGGCGCCUGAAGAGGACGAAGAGGAGAGGAGACGCCGUGAGCGGGACGACCAGAUGUACCGAGAGCGGCUGCGCACCUUGCUGGUCAUCGCGGUUGUCAUGAGCCUCCUGAAUGCUCUCAGCACCAGCGGAGGCAGCAUUUCCUGGAACGACUUUGUCCACGAGAUGCUGGCCAAGGGCGAGGUGCAGCGCGUCCAGGUGGUGCCUGAGAGCGACGUGGUGGAAGUCUACCUGCACCCUGGAGCCGUGGUGUUUGGGCGGCCUCGGCUAGCCUUGAUGUACCGAAUGCAGGUUGCAAAUAUUGACAAGUUUGAAGAGAAGCUUCGAGCAGCUGAAGAUGAGCUGAAUAUCGAGGCCAAGGACAGGAUCCCAGUUUCCUACAAGCGAACAGGAUUCUUUGGAAAUGCCCUGUACUCUGUGGGGAUGACGGCAGUGGGCCUGGCCAUCCUGUGGUAUGUUUUCCGUCUGGCCGGGAUGACUGGAAGGGAAGGUGGAUUCAGUGCUUUUAAUCAGCUUAAAAUGGCUCGUUUCACCAUUGUGGAUGGGAAGAUGGGGAAAGGAGUCAGCUUCAAAGACGUGGCAGGAAUGCACGAAGCCAAACUGGAAGUCCGCGAGUUUGUGGAUUAUCUGAAGAGCCCAGAACGCUUCCUCCAGCUUGGCGCCAAGGUCCCAAAGGGCGCACUGCUGCUCGGCCCCCCCGGCUGUGGGAAGACGCUGCUGGCCAAGGCGGUGGCCACGGAGGCUCAGGUGCCCUUCCUGGCGAUGGCCGGCCCAGAGUUCGUGGAGGUCAUUGGAGGCCUCGGCGCUGCCCGUGUGCGGAGCCUCUUUAAGGAAGCCCGAGCCCGGGCCCCCUGCAUCGUCUACAUCGAUGAGAUCGACGCGGUGGGCAAGAAGCGCUCCACCACCAUGUCCGGCUUCUCCAACACGGAGGAGGAGCAGACGCUCAACCAGCUUCUGGUAGAAAUGGAUGGAAUGGGUACCACAGACCAUGUCAUCGUCCUGGCGUCCACGAACCGAGCUGACAUUUUGGACGGUGCUCUGAUGAGGCCAGGCCGACUGGACCGGCACGUCUUCAUUGAUCUCCCCACGCUGCAGGAGAGGCGGGAGAUUUUUGAGCAGCACCUGAAGAGCCUGAAGCUGACCCAGUCCAGCACCUUUUACUCCCAGCGUCUGGCAGAGCUGACACCAGGAUUCAGUGGGGCUGACAUCGCCAACAUCUGCAAUGAGGCUGCGCUGCACGCGGCGCGGGAGGGACACACUUCCGUGCACACUCUCAACUUCGAGUACGCCGUGGAGCGCGUCCUCGCAGGGACUGCCAAAAAGAGCAAGAUCCUGUCCAAGGAAGAACAGAAAGUGGUUGCGUUUCAUGAGUCGGGCCACGCCUUGGUGGGCUGGAUGCUGGAGCACACGGAGGCCGUGAUGAAGGUCUCCAUAACCCCUCGGACAAACGCCGCCCUGGGCUUUGCUCAGAUGCUCCCCAGAGACCAGCACCUCUUCACCAAGGAGCAGCUGUUUGAGCGGAUGUGCAUGGCCCUGGGAGGACGGGCCUCGGAAGCACUGUCCUUCAACGAGGUCACUUCUGGGGCACAGGACGACCUGAGGAAGGUCACCCGCAUCGCCUACUCCAUGGUGAAGCAGUUUGGGAUGGCACCUGGCAUCGGGCCCAUCUCCUUCCCUGAGGCGCAGGAGGGCCUCAUGGGCAUCGGGCGGCGCCCCUUCAGCCAAGGCCUGCAGCAGAUGAUGGACCAUGAAGCAAGACUGCUGGUGGCCAAGGCCUACAGACACACCGAGAAGGUGCUGCAGGACAACCUGGACAAGUUGCAGGCGCGAGCACUGUGUGUCACGUGGGGAUCGUGUUUGGGGCCCUUAGACUGUCGUCCCCAGCCAGCAGCAGCCGCCUCUGGGCAGGUGUGGGCGGUGCCGUCCCCGGCUGAAGCAGGCCUGCCUGUGGACCCAUGCUCAUCACGGUUGACAAAGCAGCUCUGCAGAGCUCGGGCACAUCACAGUGGGAGCCACAACGGGAGCAAAGCUGCAGCUGGCAAACGCCCUUCUGGAAAAGGAAGUGAUAAACUAUGAGGACAUUGAGGCUCUCAUUGGCCCGCCGCCCCAUGGGCCGAAGAAAAUGAUCGCACCGCAGAGGUGGAUCGACGCCCAGAGGGAGAAACAGGACUUGGGCGAGGAGGAGACCGAAGAGACCCAGCAGCCUCCACUUGGAGGCGAAGAGCCGACUUGGCCCAAGUAGUUGGGAGGUGUUGGCUGCACGUGCGGGUGGUCCGGGAAGUGAGGGCUCACUCAGCCACCCUGAGUUGCUUUUCAGCUGAGGUUUGCACUUCCUCUCGCGGCCCUCAGUAGUCCCUGCACAGUGACUUCUGAGAUCUGUUGAUUGAUGACCCUUUUCAUGAUUUUAAGUUUCUCUGCAGAAACUACUGACGGAGUCCUGUGUUUGUGAGUCGUUUCCCCUAUGGGGAAGGUUAUCAGUGCUUCCCGAGUGAGCAUGGAACACUUCGAGUUCCCAGGGUUAUAGACAGUCGUUCCCAGUGUGGCUGAGGCCACCCAGAGGCAGCAGAGCAUUCAGACUCCAAACAGACCCCUGUUCAUGCCGACGCUUGCACGACCGCCCCAGUUCCUGUGGCUCCCUCGGAAUGCUAAGGGGAUCGGACAUGAAAGGACCCUGUGAGCCGAUUGUCCUAUCUCCAGCGGCCCUGUCAUCCAGCUCACUCAUCAAUGGGGCCAGUCAGGCCCAGGCACUGGGCUCCGGAGGACUCACCACUGCCCCCUGCUGCCAUGUGGACUGGUGCAAGUUGAGGACUUCUUGCUGGUCUAGUCACGCAUGCAGUGUUGGGGAUGCCUUGGUUUUUACUGCUCUGAGAAUUGUUGAGAUACUUUACUAAUAAACUGUGUAGUUGGAAAAUCUACA